GCAGUUGUUUGGGCUGUCCCUGUGGCUGGUUCUGGGGUGUGCGGCCAGCCAUGGAGCGCUCUGGGCCCAGCGAAGUGACAGGCUCAGACGCGUCGGGACCGGACCCGCAGCUUGCGGUCACCAUGGGCUUCACGGGGUUCGGUAAAAAAGCUCGCACAUUUGACUUGGAAGCAAUGUUUGAACAAACUCGAAGGACAGCUGUGGAAAGAAGUCGCAAAACACUGGAAGCAAGAGAAAAAGAGGAAGAAAUGAACAGAGAGAAAGAAUUAAGAAGACAAAAUGAAGAUAUUGAGCCAACAUCCUCAAGAUCAAAUGUGGUCAGAGAUUGCUCCAAAUCAUCUUCCAGGGAUACGAGCAGCAGUGAAAGUGAACAGAGUUCUGACUCUUCUGAUGAUGAGUUAAUUGGCCCUCCUUUACCCCCUAAAAUGGUAGGAAAACCAGUUAAUUUUAUGGAGGAAGAUAUCCUCGGUCCUUUACCUCCACCUCUUAAUGAAGAAGAAGAAGAAGCAGAGGAAGAAGAAGAGGAAGAGGAGGAAGAGGAAAAUCCUGUUCACAAGAUUCCUGACUCGCAUGAGAUAACGCUGAAGCAUGGCACUAAAACAGUGUCUGCUUUGGGUCUGGAUCCCUCAGGUGCCCGUUUGGUGACAGGAGGAUAUGACUAUGAUGUUAAGUUUUGGGAUUUUGCUGGAAUGGAUGCUUCUUUUAAGGCAUUUCGAUCCCUUCAGCCCUGUGAGUGCCAUCAGAUCAAGUCAUUACAGUAUAGUAACACAGGAGACAUGAUUCUUGUUGUAUCUGGAAGCUCUCAGGCCAAGGUGAUUGACAGAGAUGGUUUUGAAGUAAUGGAAUGUAUAAAAGGAGACCAGUAUAUUGUGGACAUGGCCAACACCAAGGGUCAUACAGCAAUGCUUCAUACUGGCUCAUGGCAUCCCAAAAUAAAGGGAGAAUUUAUGACUUGCUCAAAUGAUGCGACUGUGAGGACGUGGGAAGUUGAAAAUCCAAAGAAGCAAAAAAGUGUGUUUAAACCACGGACGAUGCAAGGCAAAAAAGUCAUUCCCACUACGUGCACAUAUAGUAGAGAUGGAAACCUCAUAGCAGCUGCCUGCCAGAAUGGAAGCAUACAGAUCUGGGACCGAAAUUUGACUGUUCAUCCUAAGUUCCACUAUAAACAGGCUCAUGACUCGGGCACAGACACUUCUUGCGUGACUUUUUCCUAUGAUGGUAAUGUCCUUGCCUCUCGUGGAGGUGACGAUUCAUUAAAAUUAUGGGACAUCCGACAAUUUAAUAAACCACUUUUUUCAGCCUCGGGUCUUCCCACCAUGUUCCCAAUGACUGACUGCUGUUUCAGUCCAGAUGAUAAGCUCAUAGUCACUGGUACAUCUAUUCAAAGAGGAUGUGGCAGCGGCAAACUUGUUUUCUUUGAGCGUAGGACUUUCCAAAGGGUGUAUGAAAUAGACAUCACAGAUGCGAGUGUUGUUCGCUGCCUGUGGCAUCCAAAGCUGAACCAGAUCAUGGUUGGAACUGGAAAUGGAUUGGCUAAAGUCUAUUACGACCCCAACAAGAGUCAGAGGGGAGCAAAAUUAUGUGUGGUUAAAACCCAGCGGAAGGCAAAACAAGCUGAGACUCUAACUCAGGACUACAUCAUCACCCCUCAUGCCUUGCCUAUGUUCCGUGAGCCCCGCCAACGGAGUACAAGGAAACAGCUGGAGAAGGACAGACUGGAUCCCCUGAAGUCGCAUAAACCUGAACCUCCUGUAGCAGGCCCAGGUCGUGGUGGCCGAGUUGGAACCCACGGGGGCACUCUCUCUUCCUAUAUUGUGAAGAACAUUGCUUUGGACAAGACCGAUGACAGUAAUCCUCGGGAAGCCAUUUUGCGUCAUGCCAAAGCAGCAGAAGACAGCCCAUAUUGGGUUUCUCCAGCAUAUUCCAAGACUCAGCCCAAAACCAUGUUUGCCCAAGUUGAAUCUGAUGAUGAGGAAGCAAAGAAUGAGCCAGAAUGGAAAAAACGUAAAAUUUGAAGAAUCUCAUUUGAGAGCUGUUUGCAUGAGUGGGAGGGGUAUGGGACAGGUUUGGGUUUUUUUUUUAUGCUCAUGAAAUUAAAAAUUCAUUUUUAUGAACAGGUUUUGUCCUUUGCAUUAUUGAACUGGUCAAAAGUUUGGUGGCUAGGCUUCACUAAAAUUGUGCUUAAAUUUUCUUACCUGCAACUAUUAAACUGAUUACAGAUAAACAAGAAACAGAUUCUUAGUCUAUUACCAAGUACUUUAGGUAUUUGGAAACUUUAUUCAACAAUUAUUGGUCUUGUCCAGAUUCUCAUAACCUUAGAGAGGAAAAUGUACAUUAAGAUGUGCAUCUGUCUCUAGCAAUUCUAGGAACAUAAUAUAGAAAUAGAGAUCAAAAAGUUUAAUGUUUCUGUAUAAUUUCACAACAGUUGUUUACAUGACUGUAAUUAAUUAGGCUGAGUUCAAACCAAAUACAUUGCCAUACUGGGAAAGAGCAUUAUCUCAUUAUCCUUCAAUAGCAGAAUACAGUGGUUAAGAGUUAGGAGUGGGCUUUGAAGUCAGACUCAUGUGGAUUCAAGUCCUGGCUUUGCUCUUUACUUCUGGGUCAUCUUAAGAGAGUUAUUUAACUUUUCUUUUCUAGCCUCAGAUGAUGAAAUAGUACGUACUUUGCAGGUUCGUCAGAAGAAUUAAAUGGGACAUGCCUCACAGAGCAUUUAGUACAGUACCUGGAACACAGUAAAUGUAUACCAAAUAUUUGCUAUUUUAAAAUAGGGCUAAUAUUUACUUUGCUUGGUUUUUAUCAGUAUUAAAUUAGAAAGGUAUAGAAUUGCUUUGUAAAUGUAAAGACUAAACAGAAGACAUUAAAAAUUAUUCUAAAAAA